AGCUUCCGGGUUUCCUGGGCUACUACGAUGGCGAUGAGUUUCGAGUGGCCGUGGCAGUAUCGCUUCCCACCCUUCUUUACGUUACAACCGAAUGUGGACACUCGGCAGAAGCAGCUGGCCGCCUGGUGCUCGCUGGUCCUGUCCUUCUGCCGCCUGCACAAACAGUCCAGCAUGACGGUGAUGGAAGCUCAGGAGAGCCCGCUCUUCAACAACGUCAAGCUACAGCGAAAGCUUCCUGUGGAGUCGAUCCAGAUUGUAUUAGAGGAACUGAGGAAGAAAGGGAACCUCGAGUGGUUGGAUAAGAGCAAGUCCAGCUUCCUGAUCAUGUGGCGGAGGCCAGAAGAAUGGGGGAAACUCAUCUAUCAGUGGGUUUCCAGGAGUGGCCAGAACAACUCCGUCUUUACCCUGUAUGAACUGACUAAUGGGGAAGACACAGAGGAUGAGGAGUUCCACGGGCUGGAUGAAGCCACUCUACUGCGGGCUCUGCAGGCCCUACAGCAGGAGCACAAGGCCGAGAUCAUCACUGUCAGCGAUGGCCGAGGCGUCAAGUUCUUCUAGCAGGGACCUGUCUCCCUUUACUUCUUACCUCCCACCUUUCCAGGGCUUUCAAAAGGAGACAGACCCAGUGUCCCCCAAAGACUGGAUCUGUGACUCCACCAGACUCAAAAGGACUCCAGUCCUGAAGGCUGGGACCUGGGGAUGGGUUUCUCACACCCCAUAUGUCUGUCCCUUGGAUAGGGUGAGGCUGAAGCACCAGGGAGAAAAUAUGUGCUUCUUCUCGCCCUACCUCCUUUCCCAUCCUAGACUGUCCUUGAGCCAGGGUCUGUAAACCUGACACUUUAUAUGUGUUCACACAUGUAAGUACAUACACACAUGCGCCUGCAGCACAUGCUUCUGUCUCCUCCUCCUCCCACCCCUUUAGCUGCUGUUGCCUCCCUUCUCAGGCUGGUGCUGGAUCCUUCCUAGGGGAUGGGGGAAGCCCUGGCUGCAGGCAGCCUUCCAGGCAAUAUGAAGAUAGGAGGCCCACGGGCCUGGCAGUGAGAGGUGUGGCCCCACACCGAUUUAUGAUAUUAAAAUCUCAACUCCCA